GUCUCACUUUGUGGCGGUCAUUUUGGCUGCCUUGCAGCUGUUUUACCUGUUCAGAAACUACAGAGGGCUGGGUCAGGUCUGAGGGAAAAGGAGGCGAAGGCAACAGGAAGCCUUGUCCCUACUGCACAGAGGUAAGACUGAGGCUCUGACGCUAGGCUAGGGUGCCACCCAUUGUGAUCUCGUGUCAGUGCUGGGCUGGAGGCUGCCAUGUGGCUGUCCCCAUCCUAGUCACCGCAGUUUCUGGAGCCAUUCACCCACAGGCUCGCAUCACGGUGGCUUCAAGUUGGUGGUGCGUCCCUUGGGCCCUCACCCGCCGGACUCCUACUUUCAAAUCUUAAGCCCCACAUUGUGGGAACCUGUUCAGGUCACUUCAGUCUAGGCCCUGGUGUUUAGGCUGGGGGAAGCGGGAGAGCUCAUGGGUGAUGAAGCCGUUUCUGAAAGCCAGUGUGGUGAGUCACAGAAGAUUGUUACAGACUGAGGGAUCAGCAUGUGCAAAGGUUUGGAGGCACAACUGGGCUGGCCUGGGGGCUGUGUGUACACAGAGUAGAGUGUGAAGAGAAGUCACACCUGCAGUGACAAGGUGUUGUACCUUCAUUUGUCACAGAACCAAACUGGGCCCAUUUGCCCAUAUACAAAGGAAAGUCAAACACCAGAAACCCAAACACCAAAGCAUUGGGUUUUUGCAGCAAUAAAGGUUUACUAAGAGUCAAGGAGGCAGGAGGCCAGUCUGUCUCCUUGUACCAGCUUGGCCGCCAUAGAUUUGAGGGAGAGAUUUUGAGGGUGGGGUUUUGGGCUGGACAGUGAUUGGCUGGAAGACAAAGCGGUUUGGAGAGUCCCUUGGGCAAGGACUGUUGCCCCUACAUGCUGCUUUAUGGGUCAUAUGUUCAGGAAAUGGUGUUAGCAUGAUCUGGAGGUGUUUUCAGCCCUCUAACAUCAAAAGGUCACUCAUCUGAUAAGUCUAUUCUGUGCAGACUCCAGUCAGCCAUAUUGGUCCCAAGCAGUCUCAGCUCAUCAGCCAACUUUGUUGCAAACAGAGGGGACUGUGGGAAACUAUUUACUUUUCUACUGUUCUGCAAAACAAGUUCAGGAAAUUUUGCUAGUUAACAAAUUCUCUACCCCUGGGGCACGGUUUCACUUUCUGAUGGUGCUUGGAGCCAUGCAGGGUUGUGAACUGAGGAGGAACACAGUCUGAGUUAAGGUUUUAAAGUUUCCCAAAAGCUGCUUGGAGGAAGAAGACUGGAUGAGGUGCAAGUUGGACAGUGAGGUACAGGGAGAUUGAGUACUUGUUCAAAGUUACAAAGCAGGUAAAAGGCAUUAUUGAGGACUGAAAUAUAGAGAUUGUACAGUCAGUCCAAGGUCACCUGUUUCCACCACUGGGCAGAUGUUCAAGAGAGGCCUAAGCCCAUGGAGUCCUCCCAUAGUUGCCUGCUUCUCAAGGUCUACCUCUUCCCACAGGUUCCUGUGGCCACAAAAGUGCUUAUGGAUCAUACACAGAGUAAUGUGACCUUUGAGGAAGUGGCCAUGCACUUCUCCUGGAGGGAAUGGAGUCUCCUUGAUGAUGUUCCGAAACUCCUAUACUGCAGUGUGAUGCUGAGAACUUUUCACUGAUGGCCUCAAUGGGGUAUCUUCUUCCAAAAUUGGAACUGAGCUACCUGAUGGAAAAUGAGCAAGAUUAUUGUGUGGUGAAGAGAGGCCUCUCAUAAAGUUCCUGUCCAGAUAUCCCAAAUGACCCAGCAAAAGGGACAUUUCGUUUGCCCCCUCACAGCCAUUGUAUGUGAGUGUCUUGUGAUGAUGAUGAUGAUGAUGAUGAUGAUGAUGAUGAUGAUGAUGAUGAUAAAAAUAGCCGUAAUGCAUUUCAUGAGUACUGACUUUGUGCCAGGUCCUGUGCAAAGCUCUAUUACUUCCCAUGAGGAAUCUCCAUCUCAAGGCUCAGAGAGAUGAACUGCUGGCGCAGGGAUACACAGGGAGGAAAGUCAAGGCGUGAGUUGCCUGGUAGAGACAUUUGAGAGUGGGUCAUUGCCUCAGAUAAUUUCCACGGAACUCUGUGUGCCUCUCCUUUAAGAAGAGGUGAAGCCAAUCCCUUUCUUGGGAGCCUUGAGAAGCCGCCUCACCGAGAACAGAAAGUGCGCUCCAGGCAUUAGUAUCAUUUGAAGACGUGGUUGUGACCUUCACUGGAGAGGAAUGGGGGCACCUGGACCUGGCCCAGAGGACCCUGUACCAGGAGGUGAUGCUGGAGACCUGCAGGCUCCUGGUCUCACUGGGGCAUCCUGUUCCCAAACCAGAGCUGAUCUAUCUACUGGAACAUGGACAGGAACUGUGGACAGUGAAGAGAGGCCUCUCCCAAAGCACCUGCGCAGGUGAAAAAGCAAAACCCAAGAUUACAGAGCCUACUGCUUCUCAGCUGGCCUUCUCUGAGGAAUCCUCUUUCCAGGAACUUCUGGCACAGAGAUCCUCAAGAGAUUCCAGGUUGGGGCAAGCUAGAGAUGAGGAAAAGCUAAUAAAAAUUCAGGAAGGGAACUUGAGGCCAGGAACAAACCCCCACAAAGAGAUAUGCCCUGAGAAGUUGAGUUAUAAACAUGAUGAUUUGGAGCCAGAUGAUAGUCUGGGCUUAAGGGUUUUACAGGAACGAGUCACUCCACAAGAUGCUCUCCAUGAGUGUGACUCUCAAGGACCAGGAAAAGACCCCAUGACUGAUGCAAGGAAUAACCCUUACACAUGCACGGAAUGUGGGAAAGGGUUUAGCAAGAAGUGGGCCCUUGUUCGGCAUCAACAGAUUCAUGCUGGAGUGAAGCCCUAUGAGUGCAAUGAGUGUGGGAAAGCCUGUCGUUAUAUGGCUGAUGUCAUUCGACAUAUGAGGCUUCAUACUGGGGAAAAACCAUACAAGUGUAUUGAGUGUGGGAAAGCCUUCAAACGCAGGUUUCACCUCACGGAGCACCAGCGUAUUCACACCGGAGAUAAGCCCUAUGAGUGCAAAGAAUGUGGCAAAGCAUUCACCCACCGCUCUUCUUUUAUCCAGCAUAAUAUGACUCACACUCGAGAAAAACCCUUUUUAUGCAAAGAAUGUGGGAAAGCUUUUUACUACAGCUCCUCAUUUGCUCAACAUAUGAGGAUUCAUACUGGAAAGAAACUCUAUGAGUGCGGUGAAUGUGGAAAGGCCUUCACGCACCGCUCCACAUUUAUCCAGCACAAUGUGACCCACACAGGAGAAAAACCAUUUUUAUGUAAAGAAUGUGGAAAAACCUUUUGCCUCAACUCAUCCUUCACUCAGCACAUGAGGAUUCACACUGGAGAGAAACCCUAUGAGUGCGGUGAAUGUGGAAAGGCCUUUACUCAUCGCUCCACUUUCAUCCGACAUAAGAGGACCCAUACCGGAGAGAAGCCCUUUGAGUGCAAAGAAUGUGGGAAGGCCUUUUGUGACAGCUCUUCCUUAAUUCAACAUAUGAGGAUUCACACUGGUGAGAAGCCUUAUGAGUGCAGUGAAUGUGGAAAGGCUUUUACACACCACUCUGUUUUUAUUCGACAUAAUAGGACCCACAGUGGACAAAAACCCUUGGAGUGCAAAGAAUGUGCAAAAGCCUUUUACUAUAGCUCUUCCUUCACUCGACACAUGAGGAUUCACACUGGAGAGAAGCCCUAUGUUUGUAGAGAAUGUGGAAAGGCUUUUACCCAACCUGCAAAUUUUGUUCGGCAUAAUAGGAUCCACACUGGAGAAAAACCUUUUGAAUGCAAAGAAUGUGAGAAAGCCUUCUGUGACAACUUUGCUUUAACUCAGCACAUGAGAACUCACACUGGAGAGAAACCCUUUGAAUGCAAUGAAUGUGGAAAGACCUUCAGCCACAGUUCAUCGUUCACUCACCAUCGAAAGAUUCAUACCAGAGUUUAAAAGAUACAGGAAGGCCUAUUACAAGUGUGUUUGUCUUUAGUGAACUCAUAGUGGUGACAUACCUUUCCUUUUGAGUAUAACUAUUGAGGGAAAUAUUUUGGCCAGAGAGAUGUCUUAGUAUCUGAUAAUUUAUACUAACUAGAAACAGAAUUGUCCCUGUGAAAUCUUUUUAUGGCAGGUAAUCACUUGUCAUCCAAAGAAUUAUAUUAAAGAUUCACCCAGUUUAGAGCCUUACACUGUACCUGAGAAUAAUCGAGGGGAGAGACCUGGUGGUUAACAUGCAUUUAGGUAAAAUGUCAGGAACAACUUUCCUCUUAUUAAUACUAUAAAUCCAUCUCAAGCAUAUUUUAAAAUAAUGAGAGAUGGAGGAAACAAUCUAGAAGAUAAAAGAAAAAGAUGUGCAUAACUUGUUUUCAGUUUCCCUGUUUAUGACAGUUUGUCAUUUGGCGGGUUGGGGGAUGGAGCAGGGAAUAAGACAUUGAAAAAGUCUCAUCCCCUUUGUGUGUUUUACAUAUAUAUAUCUCUAAGUCCAGAGCCAGGAGAGUUGGACCAUUGAGGGCAGCUCUGCCAACAUUUAGUAAAAGUAUUCAUUGUUCCAAAACUGUCAUCUCUACCCUUGAGGGAGUGUGUCUUUGUGAGAAAUAUAAAGGCUUGAGUCAUGAAAUACUUAACACAUGUGCACAUGUACACAUGUACAUUUAUAUGCAGUGAAUUGUUACUCGUGGUAGUUAGGUUCUGUGAAUUUUCUGUGCACACUGAAUUAGUGAAUGCUGAAUGAUUGUUGCUAGGGGAAAUACAGCGUUAGCUUCUGUGAGCCUCUGAUCCAAACAUUUUUAUCAACCAGUCAACACAUAACCUUCUUCUAUGGGUAUUUGUUUGUUUGUUUGUUUAAAGACACUUUAUCAGUGUUUCUUGAAUAAUUAUAAUUAUUCUUUAUAAUAAAAAUAUUUUAAUUAUAGCA